AGAGAGGGUCGUCACUUCCUGUCACUAGGACUACAGUUUGUAGUCUCUCUCAGGGAGAGAGACUACAAACUGUAAUUAAAAAAAUCAGAGGUGGAGGUCAGGGGGUUAGGUCCAGAAGAAAACCUCUCUGGAGCCCACCCUGCAUCUCUACGUCUUGGAAGAGUCUGGAGUCCAGGCACCCUACAGCACCCCCCACAGCAAUCAUCCGUGCUCCCACCCCCACCCCGGCCUCUGGGAGGCUCUGAGGCAACAGUGGGGGCCUGUGGGGUGGGGUGGGAUUGAGAGACCAGCUGCAGAGACAUCUUUGUGACCCAGGAGCACCACUGGUCCCUCAUCUGCCACCGAGGCCAAGGAAGACCCAGAGACCUGCCUCACCAGUGCUGCCGUUGUGCUGAAAGACAACCAUGAAUGCUGAUUUUCUGCUGCCGUAUUAUACGGCCCAGAGUGGCUCCAGCAUGAGCAUGUUCAACACCACCAUGGGGAAACUGCAGCGACAACUGUACAAGGGGGAGUACGAUAUAUUCAAGUAUGCACCGAUAUUUGAGAGCGACUUUAUCCAGAUCACCAAAAGGGGAGAAGUGAUUGAUGUGCACAACCGUGUCCGUAUGGUGACCAUGGGCAUUGCACGUACCAGCCCCAUCCUCCCACUCCCAGAUGUCAUGCUACUGGCACGACCGGCCACCGGCUGCGAAGAGUAUGCUGGACAUGGCCAGGCCACCAAGAGAAAAAAACGCAAGGCAGCAAAGAACUUAGAGCUCACCAGGCUUCUGCCCCUGAGGUUUGUACGGAUCUCUGUUCAAGACCAUGAGAAACAACAGCUGCGCCUGAAGUUCGCCACUGGCAGAUCUUGCUAUCUGCAAUUGUGUCCCGCUCUUGACACACGGGAUGACCUCUUUGCCUAUUGGGAAAAACUAAUUUACCUCUUGCGGCCACCCAUGGAGAGUAACAGCAGUACCUGUGGCAUUCCAGCUGAAGACAUGAUGUGGAUGCCUGUGUUUCAGGAAGACAGGAGGAGCCUGGGAGCCGUGAACCUUCAAGGAAAGGGGGAUCAGGACCAGGUCAGCAUCCAAAGCCUCCACAUGGUCUCUGAGGUGUGUGGGGCCACCUCUGCUGCUUAUGCUGGAGGGGAGGGACUCCAAAAUGACUUUAACAAACCCACUAAUGUGCUCAAUGCAUCCAUCCCCAAAACAUCUACAGAACUUGCUGAGGAGCCAGCAACAGGGGGGAUUAAAGAGGCAGCAGCAGCAGGGGCAGCUGCAGGGGCAGCAACAGGCACCGUAGCAGGUGCCUUGAGUGUGGCAGCAGCCAAUUCUGCCCCUGGACAGGUGAGCGCAGCCAUAGCUGGGGCGGCCACCAUCGGUGCAGGAGGAAACAAAGGCAACAUGGCCCUUGCAGGCACUGCCAGCAUGGCUCCAAACAGCACGAAGGUGGCUGUGGCAGGGGCUGCAGGCAAGUCCUCAGAGCAUGUUUCCAGCGCAUCCAUGAGCCUUUCCCGAGAGGGCAGUGUGAGCCUGGCCAUUGCAGGAGUAGUACUGACCAGCAGGACAGCUGCAGAAGCAGACAUGGAUGCAGCAGCGGGACCUCCCGUCUCCACCCGGCAGAGCAAGAGCAGCCUGAGUGGACAGCAUGGAAGGGAGCGAACCCAGGCCAGCGCUGAAGGCUGCAAGGAGGGGAGGGAAAGAAGGGAAAAGGACAGGGCUCUCGGAAGGAGUUCCCAUCGCCGCAGGACAGGUGAAAGCCGCCACAAAACAAGGGGAGACAAGAUUGCCCAAAAGUCCUCCAGCAGGUCCUCAUUCAGCCACAGAGCCAAUAGAGAUGACAAAAAGGAGAAAGGCUGUGGCAACCCGGGGAGCAGCAGGCACAGGGACUCGCAUAAAGGUGUCAGCCACACGCCCAUCUCAAAGGAGUCCAGGACCUCUCACAAAUCUGGGAGGAGCUUAUGGACCACCAGUUCCGGUUCCAGCAAGGGACUUGGCAGGGUCAGCUCUUUCCUGAGGAACGUCAGAGCCAACCUUACUACAAAAGUAGUGGGCACACCACAUGGCAGAGAUGUGAACGUCAUGGCUAAGAUGGCGGAGAGGAGCACCAACGUGGCCAUCGCCGAGACAGCAGAGGGUGGCCAGGGGCUGGAGACGGUUGGUUCUAUGACACCGGACAUCAUGGAGACAGUGACCUUUGAAGCCCAUUAAAUAAGACCCAGAGCUGGAAGCUGCAAAGGAGCCCAGAGCUCAUGGGAGUGUCCCUGGAAAGCCUAUUCCAGCGUUCUUUACUGCCGUUUAAAUAAAGAAUCAUACAUCUGAAA